AUCCCUUUCCCCUUGUGUCCGCCAUAUUGGACUCUAACUCUGGUCAGCCGCGGCGCCGGGACUGUGGACUCGCGGUUCCUCCCGCCCAGCGGCCUGCCCCGCAGCUCCCGCCCGCCCCAGCCCUCCCCGACCCGGACGCGACCCCGCGCAGCGCCCCCCGGCUGGCCGGAGCGCCCGCCGCCGCGGCCGCCUCAGCCUCCCCGCCUUCCCCGCCCUCCGCCGCCGCCCGCGGCCCCCGCGCCCGCUCUGCGCCCCUCUCCCCGCCCGCCAUGAGCCCAGCCGACGCCAAGCGCGGGGCCAAGCGCCGGAAGAACAAGCGGGGCGGCGGCGGCGGCUCGGGCGGGGGUAACGGCGGCGCGAGCAGCGGCAAGGCCGGCCCGGCGGCGGCGCUGCGCGGUUCCCAGGCCGCGGGCCUGGCGGCCCCGGGCAGCGCGGCAGGCCUGGUGGGCGGCGCGGCGGCGGCCAACGGGCCUCUCGGCGCGGGCGCGAGCGCGGGCGGCGCCGCCCCCGGAGGCUACUUCGAGACUCCUUUUAGUUUUGGCAUGAAUCAUAGGACACCACCCUACCCUGCUGGGGAUUAUUGUCUUCUGUGCAGAAGUGAACGGAAAGACUCAUCAUUCUUAGAGAGUGGAAUUAAGACUGCGAGCAAAUUGGCCCUUUCCAUGGCUCCCAAGGGCAACAGCGUGCUGCACCUGCCACUGUGGGUGUGCCCGGACUGCCGCAGGACCGUGGAGAAGGAGGAGAGGCAUGGCGGCCUUGACCAGCCAGUGAGCCAAGAUUUUCUUCUUCACUCCUCGCUUGGUGGCUCCCAGCCAGAGGCCGGCAGUGGUGGGAGGCUCGCUCUGGGUGCACAGACGCUGCCUUCAGACACCGCAUGCUCGUGCGAGGCCUGCAGUGAGCGCAGAGAAAUUUCGGCAGAGGCGGACCGGGAACCUCAGCAGCUGCAGAACUACUGGUCAGAAGUGCGCUACACGGUGCGCUGCAUCUACCGCCAGGCAGGAACCCCGCUGGCAGAUGACCAGGACCAGUCUCUGGUGCCUGACAAGGAGGGAGUGAAGGAGCUCGUGGAUAGGCUCUGCGAGAGGGACCCCUACCAGCUGUACCAGCGUCUGGAACAGCAAGCUCGAGAGUAUGUGCUGGAGAUGAAGGUCCGCCUGCUCCGGCAGCUGUCGGCUGCGGCCAAGGUGAAGGCACCAUCUGGCCUGCAGGGCCCGCCGCAAGCGCACCAGUUCAUCUCCCUCCUGCUUGAGGAGUACGGCGCCCUCUGCCAGGCCGCACGCUCCAUCAGCACCUUCCUUGGCACUCUGGAAAAUGAACACUUGAAAAAGUUCCAAGUGACGUGGGAACUGCAUAAUAAACACCUGUUUGAAAAUCUGGUCUUUUCGGAGCCACUUCUUCAGAGCAACUUGCCCGCACUGGUGUCACAGAUCAGGCUAGGAACCACCACACACGACACCUGCAGUGAGGACACAUACAGUACCUUGCUGCAGAGGUACCAGCGUUCCGAGGAGGAGCUGCGCAGAGUCGCCGAGGAGUGGCUGGAGUGCCAGAAGAGGAUCGACGCCUAUGUCGACGAGCAGAGACUUUCCUGCUGUGGCUUGUCACUGACCAGCGACUUCUUAGCCUGGACUACUGUGAGAGCAGGGUCUGGAUGCCAGGACCUUCAGACCAGUGUGAAUAAGAGCAUUGAUACUGGCACCCUUGUCCAGUCCUGGCUUCGAGGGGCUGCUAUGACAAUGAAAACCAAGCAGCGCAUGUUAACAGAAGACUGGGAGCUUUUUAAACAAAGAAGAUUCAUUGAAGAACAGUUAACCAAUAAGAAAGCAGUUACUGGCGAGAACAACUUCACAGACACCAUGAGGCACAUGUUAUCGUCCCGGCUGAGCAUGCCCGACUGCCCCAACUGCAACUACAGGAGAAGAUGUGCUUGCGAUGACUGCAGUCUCUCACACAUCCUCACGUGUGGUAUCAUGGACCCCCCCGUCACUGAUGACAUCCACAUUCACCAGCUCCCACUUCAAGUGGAUCCUGCUCCUGACUAUCUUGCUGAGAGGAGCCCGCCCAGUGUGUCAUCUGCAAGCUCGGGGUCCGGCUCCAGCUCUCCCAUCACAAUUCAGCAGCACCCCAGGCUCAUCCUCACAGACAGUGGCUCGGCACCAACUUUUUGUAGUGAUGAUGAAGAUGUUGCACCAUUGUCAGCCAAAUUUGCUGAUAUUUAUCCAUUGAGUAAUUAUGAUGAUACCGAGGUGGUGGCCAACAUGAAUGGAAUCCACAGCGAAUUGAAUGGUGGCGGGGAAAACAUGGCCCUGAAGGAUGAGUCUCCUCAGAUAAGCAGUACCAGCAGUAGUUCCUCAGAAGCUGAUGAUGAAGAAGCGGACGGCGAGAGUAGUGGGGAGCCCCCAGGGGCCCCGAAGGAAGAUGGAGUGCUGGGAAGCAGGAGCCCCAGGACAGAGGAGAGCAAAGCAGACAGUCCACCCCCAUCCUACCCAACACAGCAGGCUGAACAAGCUCCAAACACUUGUGAAUGUCAUGUUUGUAAGCAGGAAGCUUCUGGACUGACACCAUCUGCAAUGACAGCCGGAGCCCUUCCUCCUGGCCAUCAGUUCUUGAGCCCAGAGAAGCCCACACACCCUGCACUGCACCUUUACCCUCACAUCCAUGGACAUGUGCCUUUGCACACUGUUCCACACCUGCCACGCCCUCUCAUCCACCCCACCUUGUAUGCAACGCCCCCCUUCACACACAGUAAGGCUUUACCGCCAGCACCUGUUCAGAAUCACACAAAUAAGCAUCAGGUAUUCAAUGCAUCUCUUCAAGACCAUAUUUAUCCGAGCUGUUUUGGGAAUACUCCAGAGUGGAAUAGUUCUAAAUUUAUAAGUCUUUGGGGAUCAGAAGUGAUGAAUGAUAAGAACUGGAAUCCUGGCACUUUCUUGCCAGAUACAAUUUCUGGGAGUGAAAUAUUAGGGCCAACACUCUCAGAAACAAGACCGGAAGCCCUUCCACCUCCAUCUAGCAAUGAAACACCUGCAGUCUCGGAUAGUAAAGAGAAAAAGAAUGCUGCAAAAAAGAAAUGUUUAUACAAUUUCCAAGAUGCUUUCAUGGAAGCAAAUAAAGUUGUCAUGGCCACGUCAUCAGCCACGUCCUCUGUGUCCUGCACAGCUACCACAGUGCAGUCCAGCAACAGCCAGUUCAGAGUGUCAUCCAAGAGACCUCCUUCAGUAGGUGACGUGUUUCAUGGCAUCAGCAAGGAGGACCACAGACACUCGGCCCCAGCCGCCCCGAGGAAUAGCCCCACGGGCUUGGCCCCCCUCCCAGCGCUCUCGCCUGCUGCGCUGUCACCUGCUGCGCUCUCACCUGCCUCCACACCUCACCUUGCAAAUCUUGCAGCCCCAUCAUUCCCCAAAACAGCAACCACAACUCCUGGGUUUGUGGACACACGCAAGAGUUUCUGUCCUGCACCCCUACCCCCGGCCACAGAUGGCUCCAUUAGCGCCCCUCCAAGUGUCUGCAGUGACCCUGACUGCGAAGGGCACCGCUGCGAGAAUGGUGUCUACGACCCACAGCAGGAUGAUGGGGACGAGAGUGCAGAUGAGGACAGCUGCUCUGAGCACAGCUCCAGCACCUCGACCUCCACCAACCAGAAGGAGGGCAAGUACUGCGACUGCUGCUACUGCGAAUUCUUUGGGCACGGCGGGCCUCCAGCUGCACCAACAAGUAGAAAUUAUGCAGAAAUGAGGGAAAAGCUUCGCUUACGGCUGACCAAGAGGAAAGAGGAGCAACCUAAAAAAAUGGACCAGAUCUCAGAAAGGGAAAGCGUCGUUGACCAUCGGAGGGUGGAGGAUUUGUUGCAGUUUAUAAAUAGCUCCGAAACCAAACCAGUGAGCAGCACGCGUGCAGCGAAGCGAGCAAGGCAUAAGCAAAGGAAGCUGGAGGAGAAAGCUCGCCUAGAAGCAGAGGCCAGGGCCCGGGAGCACCUGCACCUCCAGGAGGAGCAGAGGCGGCGGGAGGAGGAGGAGGAUGAGGAAGAAGAGGAGGAUCGUUUCAAGGAGGAAUUUCAGCGGCUUCAGGAGCUUCAGAAGCUAAGAGCUGUAAAAAAGAAGAAGAAGGAGAGGCCAAGUAAAGACUGCCCCAAGUUGGACAUGCUCACUAGAAAUUUCCAGGCAGCAACAGAGUCUGUUCCUAACUCUGGAAACAUCCACAAUGGCUCACUAGAGCAAACUGAAGAACCAGAAACCUCUUCUCACUCCCCAUCCAGGCAUAUGAACCACUCAGAGCCCAGGCCAGGGCUAGGGGCUGAUGGGGAUGCUGCAGACCCCGUCGACACCAGAGACUCCAAAUUUCUCCUCCCCAAGGAGGUGAAUGGGAAGCAGCAUGAGCCACUCUCUUUUUUCUUCGACAUCAUGCAGCACCAUAAAGAAGGAAAUGGCAAGCAGAAGCUGAGGCAGACCAGCAAGGCCAGCAGCGAGCCAGCGAGGAGGCCCACAGAGCCCCCCAAGGCCACAGAGGGGCAGUCCAAGCCCCGGGCCCAGACUGAGUCAAAGGCUAAGGUGGUCGACCUCAUGUCCAUCACAGAGCAGAAAAGAGAGGAGAGAAAAGUCAACAGUAAUAACAAUAACAAAAAGCAGCUGAACCACAUCAAGGACGAAAAGUCAAACCCAACCCCUAUGGAGCCCACCUCUCCCGGUGAGCAUCAGCAGAACAGCAAGCUGGUGCUGGCAGAGUCCCCUCAGCCAAAGGGCAAGAACAAGAAAAAUAAGAAGAAGAAAGGAGACAGAGUCAACAAUUCAAUUGAUGAUGUCUUUCUACCUAAAGAUAUUGACCUAGACAGUGUGGAUAUGGAUGAGACAGAGAGGGAAGUGGAAUAUUUCAAAAGGUUCUGCUUGGAUUCUGCUAGACAGACCCGACAAAGACUGUCUAUCAACUGGUCCAAUUUUAGCUUGAAAAAAGCCACCUUUGCUGCCCACUGAAUGAGGACUCCCUGGAGAGGGACACGCGAGAGGCAGGCCAGGCUGCACCACCCCAAGAGCCACGCCCCUCGCUGGCGCCCCAGAGCCGUGGUGCUUGCCAAGGGCUGUGCGGAGCUGGUGCUGCCUGAAACCCCAGACCGAGAAGUUGAUGCUCGGCCCACGCCGUUAGCUCGUGUGCGUGUAGUCUGUGCGUGAGACUCCUUCGAUUGUAGCUCUGUGCUGUCGGAUUGGAACAGUAGUUCCCGCCAAGUCCUCCCACCACCGCGGCCUCGGAGGCCUGGGCCGUGGCCAGAUAGGAGUUUGCAUCAUCCACGUGGCUCCGUUGCCUCUGCAUUGCGCCCUGUCCUGUCAUGUGUCCUCACCGGGGUAUCGGCCGUCACUCAGCUCUCCUGUGCCCCUGCGUCUCACCCUAGGCGGGCUGGGCGGGGCAGGCCUCCUUUGUUCUCCACAAUCUACUGUCUCCGAGUGUACACGUUGCGCUGUUUGUGUUUGAUCCCCCUGACUUGUAGCCAGCUUGUGUAAGAUCCCUUGCAGAACGAGAAAGUUAAAAACAAGCCCACCCAGUACUCACACCAUCAAGUCUGUUAUAGAGUGUACGACUGUAUUAACACGGAGGCCUGCCUGGCUACUUUUUUAACAUAUUGUUAAGUAAUAUUAAAAUCAUGUCUUUCUUUUUGAAAGAUGGAAUACAUUAGUACAGCAGGA